GCCCCUUCUCGAGAACUCGCAGAGCUGGGCUGGUAAAAUUGCAGUGCUGAAGACACUGGACCCGCAAAAGGCUGUCCCUCCCAAACCUGGGAUUCUGGGCUCACUGAGUUCACCUGCGAGUCAGCCCUACCUGCACUGCUCUGGUCUAGUACAAACAGGCUGCUGGCAUUGAGGGACGGAGUCUCCAACUCCUGGCCUCUAGCAGUCCUCCUGUGUAGGUCUCCCAAAGUGCUAGUGUGUCCGGAAUUGGUGGGUUCUUGGUCUCACUGACUUCAAGAAUGAAGCCGCGGACCCUCGCAGUCUGCUACAAUGCUGCUGCUGCACAGAGCUGUGGUCCUCAGGCUCCAACAGGCCUGCAGACUCAAGUCAAUCCCCUCAAGGAUCUGCAUUCAGGCCUGCUCCACAAAUGAUUCAUUUCAGCCCCAGCGCCCCAGCCUCACCUUCUCUGGUGAUAACUCCAGCACCCAGGGAUGGAGAGUCAUGGGGACCCUAUUAGGUCUCGGUGCAGUGUUGGCCUAUCAGGACCAUCGGUGUAGGGCUGCUCAGGAGUCAACACACAUAUACACUAAGGAGGAAGUGAGUUCCCACACCAGCCCUGAGACUGGGAUCUGGGUGACUCUGGGCUCUGAGGUCUUUGAUGUCACAGAAUUUGUGGACCUACAUCCAGGGGGGCCUUCAAAGCUGAUGCUAGCAGCUGGGGGUCCCCUAGAGCCCUUCUGGGCCCUCUAUGCUGUUCACAACCAGUCCCAUGUGCGUGAGUUACUGGCUCAGUACAAGAUUGGGGAGCUGAAUCCUGAAGACAAGGUAGCCCCCACCGUGGAGACCUCUGACCCUUAUGCUGAUGAUCCUGUACGUCACCCAGCCCUGAAGGUCAACAGCCAGCGGCCCUUUAAUGCAGAGCCUCCCCCUGAGCUGCUGACAGAAAACUACAUCACACCCAACCCUAUCUUCUUCACCCGGAACCAUCUGCCUGUACCUAACCUGGAUCCAGACACCUAUCGCUUACACGUAGUAGGAGCACCUGGGGGUCAGUCACUGUCUCUUUCCCUGGAUGACUUGCACAACUUUCCCAGGUACGAGAUCACAGUCACUCUGCAGUGUGCCGGCAACCGACGCUCUGAGAUGACUCAGGUCAAAGAAGUAAAAGGUCUGGAGUGGAGAACAGGAGCCAUCAGCACUGCACGCUGGGCUGGGGCACGGCUCUGUGAUGUGUUAGCCCAGGCUGGCCACCAACUCUGUGAAACUGAGGCCCACGUCUGCUUUGAGGGACUGGACUCAGACCCUACUGGGACUGCCUAUGGAGCAUCCAUCCCUCUGGCUCGGGCCAUGGACCCUGAAGCUGAGGUCCUGCUGGCAUAUGAGAUGAAUGGGCAGCCUCUGCCACGUGACCACGGCUUCCCUGUGCGUGUGGUGGUUCCUGGAGUGGUGGGUGCCCGCCAUGUCAAAUGGCUGGGCAGAGUGAGUGUGCAGCCAGAGGAAAGUUACAGCCACUGGCAACGGCGGGAUUACAAAGGCUUCUCUCCAUCUGUGGACUGGGAGACUGUAGAUUUUGACUCUGCUCCAUCCAUUCAGGAACUUCCUGUCCAGUCGGCCAUCACAGAGCCCCGGGAUGGAGAGACUGUAGAAUCAGGGGAGGUGACCAUCAAGGGCUAUGCAUGGAGUGGUGGUGGCAGGGCUGUGAUCCGGGUGGAUGUGUCUCUGGAUGGGGGCCUAACCUGGCAGGUGGCUAAGCUGGAUGGAGAGGAACAGCGCCCCAGGAAGGCCUGGGCAUGGCGUCUGUGGCAGUUGAAAGCCCCUGUGCCAGCUGGACAAAAGGAACUGAACAUUGUUUGUAAGGCUGUGGAUGAUGGUUACAAUGUGCAGCCAGACACCGUGGCCCCAAUCUGGAACCUGCGAGGUGUUCUCAGCAAUGCCUGGCAUCGUGUCCAUGUCUAUGUCUCCCCAUGAGCAUGGAAAGGAGCCACCUCCACCCCUUUCCCCACCCAUUAGCCUCACUGCUUCAGAAAAAUCUUUCCCACCUUUCAACUUCUUGGAUCACAACUCUGGCCUUCCUAAGCCAUACCCAAGUACACAUAUAGCACAUUUCACCCAAGGACCUUCCCUCUUUGGACACUAUGUUACAUACCCCUCUUGGCCUUUGAACCUGUGCCAGGAAGUGUGAGCUGUUACAGCAAGGGGCUAGAAGUGAAAAAAGUAAUUCUGGAGACAAGCACUAUUUUCUCUUCCUACCCCACCUCCAUUUCUAAUGCCUACUGCCAUCAAGGCCUUGUUUUGCUUUUCUUUUUGGAUUGUUCAGAGAAAUGUGUGUGGCAUGUGUAAGAAAAGUGUAUAUACUAUCUUAUACUACCUCUCCAGGUUGCCAGAGAGUUGCGAGGAGAGCAAGGGGCACAACCGUCUCCCUUUAUAGUUCUACUUUUCUAAUAAAUAGUCUGUUUAAGAUCAUAA